AGCUGUCCCUCUGUGAUCAGCCACAUUCAAUCUAUAAACUUCCAGUGCAGAUGAUGGGGACAUCUAAUAUUGGGUCUGUUCACAUUUCAGCAGGAGGUGAAACACACAAAGAGUCCCCGGCGUGCAGUGGAGCCUCGCUGGGGGAAAUGACAGCUUGGACCAUGGGCGCCCGCGGUCUGGACAAGCGAGGAAGUUUCUUUAAGCUCAUUGACACAAUUGCCUCGGAGAUCGGAGAACUGAAACAGGAGAUGGUGCGGACAGAUGUCAACCUGGAAAAUGGCCUGGAACCCGCUGAAACCCACAGCAUGGUAAGACACAAGGAUGGUGGCUAUUCCGAGGAAGAGGACGUGAAGACCUGUGCCCGGGACUCAGGCUAUGACAGCCUCUCCAACAGGCUCAGCAUCUUGGACCGGCUCCUCCACACCCACCCCAUAUGGCUGCAGCUGAGUCUGAGUGAGGAGGAGGCAGCAGAGGUCCUGCAGGCCCAGCCUCCGGGGAUCUUCCUGGUUCAUAAAUCUACCAAGAUGCAGAAGAAAGUCCUCUCCCUCCGCCUGCCCUGUGAAUUUGGGGCCCCACUCAAGGAAUUUGCCAUAAAGGAAAGCACAUACACCUUUUCCCUGGAAGGCUCAGGAAUCAGUUUCGCAGAUUUAUUCCGGCUCAUUGCUUUCUACUGCAUCAGCAGGGAUGUUCUACCAUUUACCUUGAAGUUGCCUUAUGCCAUUUCAACAGCCAAGUCGGAGGCUCAGCUUGAAGAACUGGCCCAGAUGGGACUAAAUUUCUGGAGCUCCCCAGCUGACAGCAAACCCCCGAACCUUCCACCUCCCCAUAGGCCUCUUUCCUCCGACGGUGUCUGUCCUGCCUCCCUGCGUCAGCUCUGCCUUAUAAAUGGAGUGCAUUCUAUCAAAACCAGGACGCCUUCAGAGCUGGAGUGCAGCCAGACCAACGGGGCCCUGUGCUUUAUUAAUCCCCUUUUCUUGAAAGUGCACAGCCAGGACCUCAGUGGAGGCCUGAAACGGCCGAGCACAAGGACUCCCAACGCGAAUGGCACGGAGCGGACUCGGUCCCCCCCACCCAGGCCCCCGCCACCCGCUAUUAAUAGUCUCCACACAAGCCCUCGGCUGGCCAGGACUGAAACCCAGACGAGCAUGCCAGAAACAGUCAACCAUAACAAACAUGGGAACGUAGCUCUGCCUGGAACGAAACCAACUCCCAUCCCUCCACCCCGGCUGAAGAAGCAGGCUUCUUUUCUGGAAGCAGAGGGCGGUGCAAAGACCUUGAGCGGCGGCCGGCCGGGCGCAGGCCCGGAGCUGGAGCUGGGCACAGCUGGCAGCCCAGGUGGGGCCCCGCCUGAGGCCGCCCCGGGGGAUUGCACAAGGGCCCCGCCGCCCAGCUCUGAAUCACGGCCCCCGUGCCAUGGAGGCCGGCAGCGGCUGAGCGACAUGAGCAUUUCUACUUCCUCCUCCGACUCGCUGGAGUUCGACCGGAGCAUGCCUCUGUUUGGCUACGAGGCGGACACCAACAGCAGCCUGGAGGACUACGAGGGGGAAAGUGACCAAGAGACCAUGGCGCCCCCCAUCAAGUCCAAAAAGAAAAGGAGCAGCUCCUUCGUGCUGCCCAAGCUCGUCAAGUCCCAGCUGCAGAAGGUGAGCGGGGUGUUCAGCUCCUUCAUGACCCCGGAGAAGCGGAUGGUCCGCAGGAUCGCCGAGCUUUCCCGGGACAAAUGCACCUACUUCGGGUGCUUAGUGCAGGACUACGUGAGCUUCCUGCAGGAGAACAAGGAGUGCCACGUGUCCAGCACCGACAUGCUGCAGACCAUCCGGCAGUUCAUGACCCAGGUCAAGAACUAUUUGUCUCAGAGCUCGGAGCUGGACCCCCCCAUCGAGUCGCUGAUCCCUGAAGACCAAAUAGUUUACUCCGAAGUUCAAAACAACACCCAGCUCCACCUUCUCUCCCGGUUUGAAUGGAAAAAUCAGUUUCUCAAAGUAGCUGCUGACUGCCAGACUCAAAAAUGUCUUCGGGAGUGACAGAUUGGAGCUGCACAGUGAUUCUGUUCAGGGAUGGAGUUUGGUCCUCUGUGGGUCCAGCUGCCGCCUGCUGUGGUAACGUGUGUGUGUUACAUGUGCCGGGUGUUUCUGGACGCGUGCUUCUCUGCAGGCUGUGCAUACAUACAAAGGUAGUUUUGUUAUCUUCUGAGAGGCAGUGGGUAUUUUGUUCUGUCUUGGUUGCAAGUAAACUUUUUAUUGAGGUGUAGCAUAUGUUCAGAGAGCACAAAACUCACGUAUGCAUUGGAAUGAGUUUCCACCGCAAGCUUACCUGUGGGACAACUACCAACCCCUGGAUAAGCAGAACCUGACCAGCAUCUAGGGACCCCGGGCCCCCUGUUCUCCCUCAAGGUUACCAUCCUGCUGGCUCCUCAUCCCAUACACUUCUGUAAGCAGCACGGCUUGGGAGUAAGCAAAAACUGAAAAAGACAAGUUUGUUUUGUGUAACUUUAAAAUAAGUAACAUAGUUUGGAGGUCACAUGAAAGGUGUUUUCUCCAACUUCAAGGGGAAAUUCUUUCUUUAUAAUCUCAUUUAAAGGAUGAGUUGCUAAUGGUUACUUUGGCCAAGGCAAAUUUGAAUUUGGCAAGCAGUCUUUUCUUCCAGGGUGAGAAUGUUGAAGGUUCUUUGUUUGUUUGUUUGUUGUUUUUAAUUUUAGAAGGUUGACUCUUGAAGGUUAAUUUCAGAGACUUUAUUCACCAGGCAGCAGGAGCCUUUGGAGCUACCAAACAUUUCCAGGCGGUUCAGAAGCUACACCCCAAUUUUUUCUUUCUGAUUGGGUCCAUUUGUUGAAAGUAGUAAACAGUGUGUGAUAGAGGGCUCUUUCUCUUUCUCUGUCUCUCUCUCUCUCUCCUCUCUUUUUUCUCGUUUAAGUGAUUUUCAGCAGCUCUUUGAUUUUCUCACAAAGGAAUCAAAGCCUUGUUUGUUUUCUUGUGGUUUGACUGAGGCCAGGCCUGGUUGAUCAGGGCGUGGUUAAAGCUGGGGUGUUGCUGGAGUGAGUGGCUAAAGGAAUGUGCCCUUGUGAGGUGCCUUCUAAUUGAAAAAGACAUCAAGGAGACAGCAGAAUAUCCACACAGGCUGCCUUUUUCCCCAUCCCACCAGAGACCCGCUCUCAAGGGAGACCAUAUCUGACUCAGUAUUAACAGAAACCCAACCUGCAGGAGAAGCUUCCUCUUAGGGGCUGGGGUCAGAGGGGGGUGCAGCCAGGCAGGGGCUGAUGUCAGGCCUGAGCUAUGUGGCCAGCGGCGCCAACCAGCCCACAGUGCCUGGCCUUCCCUCCCUGCUGAUGCUGUAAGAACCAACCCAAGUUAGUCCCGGGAAGCUCUUCAGCCAGCUCCUUUUGUAGUUAAAUUCGGAUGUGGUACUUGCUCUUAGAACUCAAGGACUCACUCAUUUUCUCCAAAAAACAUGCUAAAAUUAUGUAUUUCACUACUCUAGAAGGAUGCAGCCUUUAAUUUAAAAUGAUUUAUGGAGCUUCGAGUAUAAGCCCGGCAGCCUGUCCAAGCUAUUCCAGUGGGUCCUCACCUCACCCCUGUGAACAGGCAUCGUCAUCCCUUAAGGAUUGGAGGAAGGCAAGGAGGGCUCUGCCAGGCCAUGCCAUUUGUCUGACAGCCACACUCUCUAGUAAACUAGCAGGUGCGGUAUUUGAACUUCCAUUGGAUCAGAAGCCCACGUUUGCUGAGCUCACUGUUCUGCUGCUGCUGCUUGUGUUUCUAUUUUCUCAUCAGUAGUUCAGGGGAAUUGUAACUGCAGGGACAACCCUGUGUUGAGGCAGCUCAGACUAAAGCUCUCUGUUGAGUUAUGGAUAUGGCCUCCACAAGCAUUGCCAUGCUUUUUCUGUGGGUUUGUUUGGUUUGGUUUUUUUAAACUUUUGCACUAAAAGCAGUCAGUUCCUCCUGUUUCUUCACCAGUGAAACAGCAUUCUGUUUUGAAAGUAUAGUGACAGUGCUAGGCUUUUGAAAUAAAGAAGGUGAGUGGGAGCAGAGGUCAACCUGAGAAACUCAUCACAAGUCCAGGUGGAAGGAAAGAUGCGACCCUAACUAUUAGAAAGCCAGUCCCCAUAGAGGUGCACUUUAUUAGAUUAGGCCUCUGACCAGAACAUGGACUUAGCCAGCCCACUUGUCUAUGUGGGCUUAAAAACUGGUCUAUGUCUGCUUUAAAAAAAAAAAUCUAGUUCUAUCCUCAUUUCCUAUAGCUUCUGAAGAAGAUAGCUCUGAACUAGAAGACAGAAUUCUAAUUUAAAGCCUAGAUUUAUGGAACAACUUGAAGUCAAGAAGGUAGGAGGAGAUAAUACACUGGUUUAAUCCAUGUAUGUUAGAGCAGUCAUUCUUAGGUGAAAAUGACCCUGUGAAUGCAUGCACAUGUAUCCCUUUAGUAUAUGGAGAUACUACUCAUCUGUCUUCUUCAGAGGGUGGUUCUUCAGUUACAUAGAGAAAAGCUAAUGAGAAAAACAAAUAGUUCUCAGUCACUUUCCUUUUGCCCAUGUGCUGGUGUCACUAUCCUUUCUAGCACUUUCUAGACAAGUGCAAAUGAUAAACAGUGAAUCAAUCUCAAAACCGAAAAACUGCCCCUGUAAAUGAUUAUGUUCUCUCAUGGAGAAUUUGCAUUCUAUUUAGACUACCCUUUGGAGCACUUCCAACCAAAAGCCCUGCUAUGCAGAGGUUCCUGAAUACAUGUUCAUUGCCUGGCACCAGCUUGGCUCUCCUGGUUGGAGAGACACGGGCUCGUUCCUGUGUGUGCCAGCUCUCUAUUCAUUCCAGGCCACAUACUGGGCUUCCCUCCCAGAGAGCCAUCACCUACUCUCACCCUUCCAGAGUGGUACAUGGAAGAACAGACAAAUGCUUUAAUAAGAAGUGUGCAGUUUGGGGGCCCUACUUAAAGUAUUGGGAUCAACCUCUUCACGGACAGUGUGCUGCGCUCAUUACUGAUGACCCAUGCUAUAGGAUGUAGAUGGGGUGAAAUCACUUCCUGCUUCAACACACGUUCCUCACUGGUGGGUGUUCACAUCCCACCACUCUUGCUUUAGUCUUUUUCAACCCAUGGGGGAUAUCCAACCAAAGUUUCUGGUAGAGAAAUCUUCAUUUUGCAGAACUUGUUGCAAUGGUGUGGUUAGUGUUUUCAUUUUAGUAAAAUGAUGUUUAUUUCUGACUUGAUGUCAGUCUUGGGAAAUCCCUCUGUUUUCAAGGCUUGUUUCAAGAAAAACAAAAUUUGUCCAAAUCCAAACAUGUUAGUAAUCUUAAAUUUUCUAUUUCAUUCAGAUACUCUCCACAGACUAUCAGCAGUGAUACAAAAGAGCCAACUAUUCAUAUUCCUAGAAGUCAGUAGCAGAAAAGAGACAGUACUGUGCUUAUUUAAGUGCUACAAACCAAAAUGUAUGUUUUCUCCAAAGAGCAAUUUAACAAUUUGAAGAAAAAGUACCCUUAAAGUCAAUUUCCACAUAUUUCAAAGGUCACUUCGAUUUACGUAUCUGAGUGUUUUUUGUUUGUUAAUAGAGAAAUGAUACGGAAAAUGUGGUUAGACACCGGAGAGUAUAGCGCAUAUAGAAAAGGUGAUUGAAAUGAUUCCCGGGGAGUUAAACAAUCACAACUACUCUGGUUCAGAUCUGGGUUUUUUUUGUUUUUGUUUUUGUUUUCAAAUGAGUAUUUAAGCUGGCUCUAGCUUCAAUAUCUAGUGUGACUUGUUUUUAAUUUUUCAGGUCACAGUUUGGUUCAAGCCCCUGAGUUAUCUGGGUUAUUUUUUAAGAUAAAGAGCUAUUCUGGGGCCAGGUGCAGUGGCUCACACCUGUAAUCUCAGCACUUAAGGAGGCCGAGGUGGGUGGAUCACCUGAGGUCAGGAGUUUGAGACCAGCCUGGCCAACAUGGUGAAACCCAGUCUCUACUAAAAAUACAAAAAAAUUAGCCAGGCAUGAUGGUGGAUGCCUGUAAUCCCAGCUACUCAGAGGCUGAGGCAGGAGAAUCACUUGAACCCGGGAGGCGGAGGUUGCAAUAAGCCGAGAUCAUGCCAUUGCACUCCAGCCUGGGCAACAAGAGUGAAACUCCAUCUCAAAAAAAAAAAAAAAAAAAAAACUCUUCUGAGAGGUGUAGCCAGGGAGGCAUGUUAGUGCCAAACAGAGAUUAAAACCUUGAAUCUUC